GAGUUAAUUUGUGACUUCGUAACAAUAAGAAGUUAUUAUCUAAUUUAGUAAAGACCCUGAUCUGUUGCAUGUUUUUUAUUUGAUAGUUUGAAUAGAAAUUUAAUUUUCUAAGUUUUACUUUUUGUUUCUGGCUUUUAUGGCUUAAGGUUUUCUUUGGUUCUUACAUUAGAAAAUCAUUUUUAACCUCCAUUAUCAUUUUUCUAAGGUUCUUUCCUUUUUCUUAGUUGCUUUCUAUUCUGUUUUGCCUGUCUUAUUUAUUCUCAUUUGUGAUUAUUUAGAUCUUAAGACCAAACUUUCUUGGUAUAACAGUCCUAAAGAUUACAAAAUAAAAAUAUAGAGAGAGUAAAAGUAAAAAGUAAAGUAAAAAGAGAGAAGGUAUGAUUUUACUGCUAGAGAAGUUUGUCUCUGAAGAAGCACAAAAGAAAAUAUUAGUGAAUUUAAAAUAAUUUUUAUACUGCUGUAGCAUAAUUUCUAAAUUUGAAAAAAAUGCAAUGGUAAUAAAAUGUAUAAAAAUUAGAAAACUGUCAUUGUGUUAAACUAUUACAUUUAAAUGAUUACAUUUAACACAAUAGCUGUCUCAUAAAAAAUCUAAGAACUUGUAGAAUUAUUUGUAAGGUAUAUUUAGUGUUUUUUUCUCUUUUUUCAAAUGUUGCAUAGUGGUCCAGAUCAUCUAUAAUUAAUUAUAAGUUUCUUAUGAUUUACAUAAGGAUAAUUUGGAUUCUACUCUUGCUGCAUAUUCAGAAAAAUAUUAUUUACUGUUAAUUCUGAUAUGAAUUGUAUUUAAUUUGUUGUCCUAAUAGUUUUUAAUUGGUUCAUUUAAUUUUAAAGCAUAGGUUAAAUAUCUUUAUUUUUUUUAAAAUACAAGGGUCCUUCUGUACUUUUCAUUUGAAUCAUAUCCUCUAACUACUCUGUAAGAAACGUUUUUACAUCAAUAUUUUGAUUGAUUUUAUUGCUAUACCAAUACAGUCAUUAAUUUUACUUGGUGUUUUCUUCACCAUAUGUCUGUUUGAUUUAAGUGAAUUUAGAUUUGUACAGUUCUGGAAAUUUUUUAAAAAAUAUUAUGCAGAGUAAAACAUUUUAAAUUACUAUUUGUUCUAUAGAGGAGAUACAUUCUGUUUCUCUUUUGAAAUUGCAUGCAUUUUCAACCAAAUAUGAAAAAGUUUAAGUGGAUAGAUAAGACUGAAGAAUAAAAGGGUCUAUAAAAUAAAAGAGACAAAACGUUAAAGAAAGAAAUGAAUGAAUGAACCAAAAAUUCUAGGGAAAAUCAAUUUAUCUUUCCAAUUUAGACAUCUUGAGACAGCCUAGCCUAGUGCUACCCUAUACAAUUUUCUGUGAUAAUGACAGUGUUCUAUGAUGUCCAGUCCCAUAGCCAGUGGCUAAAAGUGGCCAUUGAGCACUUGAAAUUUGGCCUUUGCAACUGAAAAAACUAAAUUUUUGAUUUUAUUAAAUUUAAUUUUGAUAACCAUCCUGUUAGAUAAUGCAGAUCUGUCCCAUUCUCACAAGUAUGUGUUUAAAGAACUCAAUUUGCCUUUUCUUAAAGAUCUAUAUAAAUAAUUACCCCAUUAUAUAUAUGUAGUAGCCCUUUCUUAAUGUAAUUUUAACCUGUUUAUUUCUAAUCUUCUCUCCCUAAAGAAGAAAGUCCGUACUGCAGCUUUGAAGAAGAUUUCCCAUGCUGUCAACAUAAUGUUGCCUUCCUGGCUAUCAUUCUCUCAUCGGAUCCUCAAUUUAGGUCAUUUCUACUUCAUAUGAUCAUUUUAAUUGUAUUUACCUCAUCUUACCAAAAAGAUCAUGGUUGAAUCUUGCCUACUCACGUUUAGGGCCUUUUUUUGGUGGAUUGCUUUAAUAAAGAUGGAUCUGUCAGACCUUGGAGAAGCCGCAGCCUUCCUCAGAAGAAGUGAAGCUGAGCUGCUUCUACUACAGGCCACAGCCUUGGAUGGGAAGAAGAAAUGCUGGAUUCCUGAUGGUGAGAAUGCUUAUAUCGAGGCUGAGGUAAAAGGGAGUGAAGAUGAUGGAACAGUAAUUGUUGAGACAGCAGAUGGAGAGAGUCUGAGCAUAAAGGAGGACAAAAUCCAGCAGAUGAAUCCUCCAGAGUUUGAAAUGAUUGAAGACAUGGCAAUGCUGACUCACCUCAAUGAGGCAUCCGUGCUGCAUACCCUGAAGCGGCGCUAUGGCCAGUGGAUGAUCUAUACAUAUUCAGGUCUCUUCUGUGUGACCAUAAACCCUUACAAAUGGCUUCCCGUGUAUCAGAAAGAAGUCAUGGCCGCCUACAAAGGGAAGAGGCGAUCAGAGGCUCCCCCUCACAUCUUUGCUGUUGCCAAUAACGCCUUUCAGGACAUGCUUCACAAUCGAGAAAAUCAGUCUAUACUCUUCACAGGAGAAUCUGGUGCUGGAAAGACUGUGAACAGCAAACAUAUUAUCCAGUAUUUUGCCACCAUAGCAGCCAUGAUUGAAUCCAGGAAAAAGCAGGGGGCGUUAGAAGAUCAAAUCAUGCAAGCGAAUACUAUCUUGGAAGCAUUUGGAAAUGCUAAAACCCUGAGAAAUGACAACUCCUCUCGUUUUGGCAAAUUCAUCAGGAUGCACUUUGGUGCCAGAGGCAUGCUGUCAUCUGUGGACAUUGAUAUCUAUUUGCUUGAAAAGUCCAGGGUGAUUUUCCAGCAGGCUGGAGAGAGGAACUACCACAUAUUCUAUCAAAUUCUAUCUGGACAAAAAGAGCUUCAUGACCUGCUCCUGGUAUCUGCAAAUCCCUCAGACUUCCACUUUUGCUCCUGUGGAGCAGUUACUGUGGAGAGCUUGGAUGAUGCUGAAGAAUUGCUGGCCACAGAACAAGCCAUGGACAUCUUGGGCUUUCUUCCUGAUGAGAAGUAUGGAUGCUAUAAACUCACUGGAGCCAUCAUGCACUUUGGAAAUAUGAAAUUUAAACAGAAACCUAGAGAAGAGCAACUGGAAGCAGAUGGCACAGAAAAUGCUGACAAAGCUGCUUUCCUCAUGGGCAUUAACUCCUCUGAGUUGGUAAAGUGCUUGAUCCAUCCUAGAAUCAAAGUUGGUAACGAAUAUGUUACCAGAGGUCAAACUAUAGAACAGGUAACCUGUGCUGUCGGUGCCCUGUCCAAGUCAAUGUAUGAAAGGAUGUUUAAGUGGCUAGUGGCACGGAUCAACAGGGCCCUGGAUGCCAAGCUGUCAAGGCAGUUCUUCAUUGGCAUUCUUGACAUCACUGGUUUUGAAAUCCUUGAGUAUAAUAGCCUUGAGCAACUUUGCAUUAAUUUUACCAAUGAAAAAUUACAACAAUUCUUCAAUUGGCACAUGUUUGUUCUGGAGCAAGAGGAAUAUAAGAAAGAAAGCAUUGAAUGGGUGUCUAUUGGCUUUGGUCUGGAUUUGCAAGCUUGCAUAGAUCUCAUUGAGAAGCCAAUGGGCAUCCUUUCCAUCCUUGAAGAAGAGUGUAUGUUUCCUAAGGCUACAGACCUGACUUUCAAGACCAAACUCUUUGACAACCAUUUUGGAAAGUCGGUUCAUCUCCAGAAGCCCAAGCCUGAUAAGAAGAAAUUUGAAGCUCAUUUUGAACUUGUCCAUUAUGCAGGAGUGGUACCUUAUAAUAUCAGUGGUUGGCUGGAAAAGAACAAAGACCUCCUUAAUGAAACAGUGGUAGCUGUAUUUCAGAAGUCUUCCAACAGACUCCUGGCGAGCCUUUUUGAAAAUUACAUGAGUACUGACAGUGCUAUACCAUUUGGGGAGAAGAAACGAAAGAAAGGAGCUUCAUUCCAAACGGUUGCAUCUCUGCAUAAAGAAAACCUGAAUAAAUUGAUGACUAAUCUGAAAUCAACAGCACCUCAUUUUGUGAGAUGCAUAAAUCCCAAUGUGAACAAAAUACCAGGUAUACUGGACCCUUACUUGGUUCUACAGCAGUUGCGCUGUAAUGGUGUCUUGGAAGGGACUAGGAUAUGCCGUGAAGGUUUUCCAAACCGACUGCAGUAUGCUGAUUUUAAACAAAGGUACUGCAUUCUGAAUCCAAGGACCUUUCCAAAGAGCAAGUUUGUGAGCAGCAGAAAAGCAGCUGAAGAAUUACUUGGCUCCUUGGAGAUAGACCAUACCCAGUACCGAUUUGGAAUCACUAAGGUGUUUUUUAAAGCUGGGUUUCUGGGCCAACUGGAAGCAAUAAGAGAUGAGAGACUAUCUAAAGUCUUCACAUUGUUCCAAGCCAGAGCACAGGGCAAACUGAUGCGAAUCAAAUUCCAGAAGAUUCUGGAAGAAAGGGAUGCACUUAUUUUGAUCCAAUGGAACAUAAGAGCUUUCAUGGCUGUGAAGAACUGGCCCUGGAUGAGGCUCUUCUUCAAGAUCAAGCCUCUUGUUAAAUCUUCAGAAGUAGGAGAAGAAGUAGCUGGACUGAAGGAAGAGUGUGCACAAUUACAGAAAGCCUUGGAGAAAUCAGAGUUUCAGAGGGAGGAACUGAAAGCAAAGCAAGUAUCCCUCACUCAGGAAAAAAAUGACCUGAUUCUUCAGCUUCAGGCUGAGCAAGAGACACUGGCAAAUGUUGAAGAGCAGUGCGAGUGGCUGAUUAAAUCCAAGAUCCAGCUGGAGGCCAGAGUAAAGGAGCUGUCGGAGAGGGUGGAGGAAGAAGAGGAGAUAAAUUCUGAGCUGACUGCCAGGGGGCGGAAACUCGAAGAUGAAUGUUUUGAGUUGAAGAAAGAAAUCGAUGACCUGGAAACAAUGUUGGUGAAGUCAGAGAAGGAGAAGCGUACUACAGAGCACAAGGUCAAGAACUUGACUGAGGAAGUAGAGUUUCUAAAUGAGGAUAUCAGCAAACUUAACAGAGCAGCCAAGGUUGUGCAGGAGGCCCAUCAGCAGACCCUGGAUGACCUGCACAUGGAGGAGGAGAAGCUCAGCAGCCUGAGCAAAGCAAAUCUGAAGCUGGAACAGCAAGUUGAUGAGCUUGAGGGUGCCCUUGAGCAGGAGAGAAAAGCGAGAAUGAACUGUGAAAGGGAACUGCACAAACUGGAGGGCAAUUUAAAGCUGAAUCGGGAAAGUAUGGAGAACCUGGAAAGCAGCCAGCGACACCUGGCAGAAGAGCUGAGGAAAAAAGAAUUAGAAUUGAGUCAGAUGAAUUCAAAAGUGGAGAAUGAGAAAGGCCUGGUAGCUCAGCUUCAGAAGACGGUUAAAGAGCUUCAGACUCAAAUAAAGGAUUUGAAAGAGAAACUAGAAGCUGAAAGGACCACUCGAGCCAAGAUGGAAAGGGAGAGAGCUGACCUCACCCAAGACCUGGCUGACUUGAAUGAGAGGCUGGAGGAGGUAGGAGGAUCCAGUUUGGCUCAGCUGGAAAUAACUAAGAAACAGGAAACCAAAUUCCAGAAGCUGCACCGAGACAUGGAAGAGGCCACUCUGCACUUUGAGACAACUUCUGCAUCUUUGAAGAAGAGACAUGCAGACAGCCUGGCUGAGCUCGAGGGCCAGGUAGAAAAUCUACAGCAGGUCAAGCAGAAACUGGAAAAAGACAAGAGUGACUUGCAGCUAGAAGUAGAUGACCUCCUGACCCGUGUUGAGCAGAUGACAAGAGCUAAGGCAAAUGCUGAGAAACUCUGUACUCUAUAUGAAGAGCGCUUGCAUGAAGCAACUGCAAAGCUAGAUAAGGUGACUCAGUUGGCAAAUGACCUGGCAGCACAAAAGACAAAGCUGUGGAGUGAGAGUGGCGAGUUCCUACGGAGGCUUGAAGAGAAGGAGGCUCUGAUAAACCAACUUUCCAGGGAAAAGAGCAACUUCACUCGGCAGAUUGAAGACCUGAGAGGGCAGCUGGAAAAGGAGACCAAAUCCCAGAGUGCCCUGGCCCAUGCCCUGCAGAAGGCUCAGCGUGACUGUGACCUUCUACGAGAGCAGUAUGAGGAAGAACAAGAGGUCAAGGCUGAGCUGCACCGGACCUUAUCCAAAGUCAAUGCUGAAAUGGUGCAAUGGAGAAUGAAGUAUGAAAACAAUGUCAUCCAGAGAACAGAAGACUUGGAGGAUGCCAAGAAGGAACUGGCAAUUAGAUUGCAGGAGGCAGCCGAAGCCAUGGGGGUGGCCAAUGCCAGAAAUGCCUCCUUGGAGAGAGCCAGGCACCAGCUGCAGCUGGAGCUCGGGGACGCCCUGUCUGACCUCGGGAAGGUCCGCUCUGCAGCAGCCAGGCUGGACCAGAAGCAGCUGCAGUCUGGCAAGGCCCUUGCCGACUGGAAGCAGAAGCACGAGGAGUCCCAGGCGUUGCUGGAUGCCUCUCAGAAGGAAGUUCAGGCUCUCAGUACAGAGCUCCUCAAGCUCAAGAACACCUAUGAGGAGAGCAUCGUGGGCCAGGAGACACUCAGGAGGGAGAACAAGAACCUCCAAGAAGAGAUUUCUAAUCUGACAAACCAGGUUAGAGAAGGGACCAAGAACUUAACUGAAAUGGAAAAGGUCAAGAAACUAAUUGAAGAAGAGAAGACAGAAGUCCAGGUGACACUGGAAGAAACAGAGGGAGCCCUGGAACGUAAUGAAAGCAAGAUUCUUCAUUUCCAGCUUGAACUCUUGGAAGCUAAAGCAGAACUUGAAAGAAAGCUUUCAGAGAAAGAUGAAGAAAUAGAAAAUUUUAGGAGGAAGCAGCAGUGUACCAUUGACUCCCUGCAGUCUAGUCUGGAUUCUGAAGCUAAGAGCAGAAUUGAGGUUACCCGGCUGAAGAAGAAGAUGGAAGAGGACCUCAAUGAGAUGGAACUCCAGCUUAGCUGUGCCAACCGGCAGGUGUCAGAAGCAACCAAAUCCCUGGGCCAGCUUCAGAUUCAAAUCAAGGACCUUCAAAUGCAGCUGGAUGACAGCACACAACUGAACAGUGAUCUGAAGGAGCAGGUGGCUGUGGCUGAGCGGCGCAACUCUCUUCUUCAGUCUGAACUAGAGGAUCUAAGGUCCCUGCAAGAGCAGACAGAGCGUGGCCGCAGGCUGUCAGAAGAAGAGCUCCUGGAAGCAACAGAAAGAAUCAAUCUUUUCUAUACCCAGAACACAAGCCUCCUCAGCCAGAAGAAGAAACUGGAGGCUGAUGUUGCCCGGAUGCAGAAAGAAGCUGAAGAGGUGGUGCAGGAGUGUCAAAAUGCAGAAGAGAAGGCCAAGAAGGCAGCCAUUGAGGCAGCAAACUUGUCAGAAGAACUGAAGAAGAAGCAAGACACCAUUGCCCACUUGGAAAGGACAAGAGAAAAUAUGGAGCAGACAAUUACAGACUUACAGAAAAGGCUGGCUGAAGCUGAACAGAUGGCCCUGAUGGGGAGUAGAAAGCAAAUCCAGAAACUAGAAUCCAGGGUUCGUGAACUGGAAGGUGAACUGGAGGGUGAAAUCCGUCGCAGUGCAGAGGCCCAGAGGGGAGCCCGCAGACUUGAGCGAUGCAUCAAAGAGCUGACCUAUCAGGCAGAGGAAGACAAGAAGAAUCUGAGCAGGAUGCAAACUCAGAUGGAUAAACUUCAGCUAAAAGUGCAAAAUUACAAGCAGCAAGUCGAGGUGGCGGAAACACAAGCCAAUCAAUACCUUUCCAAGUAUAAGAAACAGCAACAUGAGUUGAAUGAAGUGAAGGAAAGGGCAGAGGUGGCAGAAUCUCAAGUCAAUAAACUCAAAAUUAAAGCAAGAGAGUUUGGGAAAAAGGUUCAAGAAGAAUAGCAUCCCCUGCUUUGAAAGGACAACAGCUGGAGAAGUACAAGGAAGGUGCUGUUUCAUGGCCAAAAACUUAGGUUGCAUGGAAACAUUUUUAAAAACAUGUUUAAAUUGCUUUUCACACCAUAUAAACAAGGCAAUUAGAAAAAUAAUUAAAGGGAAUAUCAUUGCUUCCACAGUUAAUGGGGAUUUUUUGAUCCUCAAAUGCAAGUAAACUACCUUCUAAUGCUUCACAUGACAGAUUAAAUAAAUGGAAGAACCUUUUCAAUUCUGAUGUUUAAAAAAUGAAUAAAUACUUGAUCCUUUGUCCAUAUUUCCUCUUAAUGGGUAGGACUCAUAGAAGAUGUCCUUAGACCAGUCACGCUUCAUGGGGACUAGGGCAUGUUGGUGAAUGGUUUUUACUAAAGUUAGGCAACUUUGGCUUGAUUCACCCCUAAAUCUAUGAAUGUAUAUUGUGAGCCAGCAGUGGUAGAAUGGAAGUCAUAAGAUCUCCUCAGCAUUGUGAUAUAAAUAUAGCUAUAGUUAGGCAAUUUGAACAUGUAGGCAAAACUCUCCUAAUCAACACACAUGUAGGCUAUAUGCUGGUACAUGCUUUAAACAUGGAGGUAACCCCACACGAGACAUUCAGUGACAGGUAAUAUGCUGGAUUUGUGCAGUACCGAUUUGGCUCAGCUGGAGGAACAUGUCCCGGAAUUCCUCUCUCUCAUGGUUCUGGAUUGGAGUAGGUCAUAAAGAAAUUUGCAUUAAUUUGAUCAGCAGCUAUUUUAUACUCAUAAGGUCAGUGUACAGACCCAAGCAUGGUGACAGCUUGAAAAUAUGACUCCAGGCCAAAAAGGGGAGCUAGAAGAGACCAGAGACAGCUCCCUGGACCCAGAGCUCUUCCAGCUCCUGCCAGCCUCCUCCUUCAGCUUUGCAAAGUACUGGCCAGGUGUGUGUGCAGCUCCAUGGCAACCAGCAUCAGCUUUUCCUGAGAUCACACACAGCAUUGCAGUGGAGGCCGUGAGACAGACAUGGGUUCUGUUUGUUCUUAUGGACUUCCCUUCAUCCUUGCUGCAUUCACAGUCGACCUACAGUGACUUCAGGCCCAGAACCAGAUGCAGAGGGAACAGCCUGGCCUAGACUUCUCCACCAGCACCCACAAUUGUGUAAGGCUGAAGCUCUAUAAUAAAUCUUUAUUCUGUCA